GGUUAGAUGGCUGUUAUUCUAGGUGGCAGACAUGCGGGUUUCCCUCCCUUUGCACAACUAAACAAGGCAUGUGCUGGUGGAGGUCAAAGAAACAGGAACACAAGUGAAAUCGAGGUGAGUGUCAGGUAAGGACCAAAGCACCACGCCUACCUCAUCUUUGCCCACAGAACACCCAUUCUUCCCGUGUCCUGUUUCCCAGGACGUAUCCGGGGCGGAUAAGAAAUCACCCGUGGGGAGGCGGUGAACUCCUCCGCAGGGGCCGAUGCCCGGGACAGGGGCGGGGAAGGCUAAUGAGGCGACUUGUGCGGGGAGGGGCCAAGGAGGAGCCCAGGUGUCCCGCUCCCGCUCGACGGCGCGCGCCUGCGCGAGCCCAGUUGGCGUCGCACCCUUGAGCGCAGCAUCCCUACGCCAGCGAGUCCCAAUACUAGGGAGGGAGGGAGGGAGGAGGGGCGGCCGGCCCCCCGCCCCCGCGCGCGGCCACGUGACGCCGGCUGAGGAGAUUGGAGGGGCGGCUGCGCGAGGCUGCAGACUGGUGCAGCGCACUGUGCUGGCGGCUGGGCCUCCUCCACCUCCUCGUCUUUCUCCCGGGAACCUUGACGACGCCUUCCGCUUGGCCCUGCCUUCUGCCGCAUCCCCGCCGCCGCGGCGCCUUGAGGAGCAGGAGAAGACGCAGCCGGGCCGCCGCCGUUAG